AAUCCUCCCGGGAGCCGAGGAGGCUCGCGCGCGUGCAUCCCGCACCAUCCCCCGGCCCCGGGCCCUGGCCGGCGUCAGACCGAGCUGCCGCCGCCACCACCGCAGCAGCAGCAGUCGGGGAGCCAGGCCCAGCCAGGGCCGCGGGAGGCGGGGGCGCCCGGGCCCUGGAUGUCCCGCAGCGCGGCGGCCAGCGGCGGACCCCGGAGGCCUGAGCGGCACCUGCCCCCAGCCCCCUGUGGGGCCCCGGGGCCCCCAGAAACCUGCAGGACGGAGCCAGACGGGGCGGGCACCAUGAACAAGUUACGGCAGAGCCUGCGGCGGAGGAAGCCAGCCUACGUGCCCGAGGCGUCGCGCCCGCACCAGUGGCAGGCAGACGAGGACGCGGUGCGGAAGGGCACGUGCAGCUUCCCGGUCAGGUACCUGGGUCACGUGGAGGUAGAGGAGUCCCGGGGAAUGCACGUGUGUGAAGAUGCGGUGAAGAAGCUGAAGGCGAUGGGCCGAAAGUCCGUGAAGUCUGUCCUGUGGGUGUCAGCCGAUGGGCUCCGAGUGGUGGACGACAAAACCAAGGAUCUUCUGGUCGACCAGACCAUCGAAAAGGUCUCCUUUUGUGCUCCUGACCGCAACCUGGACAAGGCUUUCUCCUAUAUCUGUCGUGACGGGACUACCCGCCGCUGGAUCUGCCACUGUUUUCUGGCACUGAAGGACUCCGGCGAGAGGCUGAGCCACGCUGUGGGCUGUGCUUUUGCCGCCUGCCUGGAGCGAAAACAGCGACGGGAGAAGGAAUGUGGGGUCACGGCCGCCUUCGAUGCCAGCCGCACCAGCUUCGCCCGCGAGGGCUCCUUCCGCCUGUCUGGGGGUGGGCGGCCUGCUGAGCGAGAGGCCCCGGACAAGAAGAAAGCAGAGGCAGCAGCUGCCCCCACUGUGGCUCCUGGCCCUGCCCAGCCUGGGCACGUGUCCCCGACACCAGCCACCACAUCCCCUGGUGAGAAGGGUGAGGCAGGCACCCCUGUGGCUGCAGGCACCACUGCGGCCGCCAUCCCCCGGCGCCAUGCACCCCUGGAGCAGCUGGUUCGCCAGGGCUCCUUCCGUGGGUUCCCAGCACUCAGCCAGAAGAACUCGCCUUUCAAACGGCAGCUGAGCCUACGGCUGAAUGAGCUGCCAUCCACGCUGCAGCGCCGCACUGACUUCCAGGUGAAGGGCACAGUGCCUGAGAUGGAGCCUCCUGGUGCCGGCGACAGUGACAGCAUCAACGCUCUGUGCACACAGAUCAGUUCAUCUUUUGCCAGUGCUGGAGCGCCAGCACCAGGGCCACCACCUGCCACAACAGGGACUUCUGCCUGGGGUGAGCCCUCCGUGCCCCCUGCAGCUGCCUUCCAGCCUGGGCACAAGCGGACACCUUCAGAGGCUGAGCGAUGGCUGGAGGAGGUGUCACAGGUGGCCAAGGCCCAGCAGCAGCAGCAGCAGCAACAGCAACAGCAGCAGCAGCAGCAGCAGCAACAGCAGCAAGCAGCCUCAGUGGCCCCAGUGCCCACCAUGCCUCCUGCCCUGCAGCCUUUCCCCGCCCCCGUGGGGCCCUUUGACGCUGCACCUGCCCAAGUGGCCGUGUUCCUGCCACCCCCACACAUGCAGCCCCCUUUUGUGCCCGCCUACCCGGGCUUGGGCUACCCACCGAUGCCCCGGGUGCCCGUGGUGGGCAUCACACCCUCACAGAUGGUGGCAAACGCCUUCUGCUCAGCCGCCCAGCUCCAGCCUCAGCCUGCCACUCUGCUUGGGAAAGCUGGGGCCUUCCCGCCCCCUGCCAUACCCAGUGCCCCUGGGAGCCAGGCCCGCCCUCGCCCCAAUGGGGCCCCCUGGCCCCCUGAGCCAGCGCCUGCCCCAGCUCCAGAGUUGGACCCCUUUGAGGCCCAGUGGGCGGCAUUAGAAGGCAAAGCCACUGUAGAGAAACCCUCCAACCCCUUUUCUGGCGACCUGCAAAAGACAUUCGAGAUUGAACUGUAGCCCGAGCCGCCCCACCCACUCCAUCAUCUCCAGGUGCCCCACGCCUGGGGGUGGAGGCACAACCUCUCCCCUAACCCUGCUCCCUGGGGCUGCGCCCCUCAACACCCUCUCAACACCCCCCUCCCUCAACCACCCCGACAACCACUACAGAACCAACAUUGUGACGCCCAGGUUGCAACAGGAUGGAAUUCAGGGACGGACCCAGCCUGGCUAAGGGAACCAUUUCACUGCCGGACUUAGGCUGGCAAUGCCCCCUUCCCCAACCCCAGACACAGGGGUUGGCCACAAUCCCACUGAAUGCCCUUGGUUCACACUCCAUUUCCCAGUUUCUGUUGACCCCCACCUUCCAGUGUUGGACAGGAUGGAGGGGGGACACUUGCUUAGGGGCUCUCCUGGGCCCCACACCAGUGCCCACCCCAAAUCUGGUCGUCUCCUCCCCCCAUGCACAGCACAAGCUAAGGGCUGCCCUCUGCCCACACGCUGCGUUCACUGCCAAUGCUGUACUCACCUCCAUCACCCUCCAACUUUGGGGCCCAUGUCUUCCUUGGGCCAAGGUCUCAUGGGGGCUAGGGCCAAGUUGGGGGCCCAGGAGGCGGGGAGGGAGGAGGAGGAGAAGAUGCGCAGUUACCUCAUGUCGGUGCCCGCUGGGGAGGGGUCCGGGAAGAAGGGGAAGGGGUGCCUGGCGGGUACUUUUCUAUCUUUUAUUUCCAGAUUUUUUUUGUAUCUAAACUUGAAGAUUUGUAUUAUACAAGGACAGCCAAUAAAGGAAGAAUAUAAUGGUGCCCCUCGGGAAACGAGGGUGUGUGUAGGGCGCUGGUGAGGCCCUAGAACCUUUCCUCCUGAGUCAUGGACUGAAACAGAGUCAGAAGGAUGUCCCUGAGUGAUAACCUCUGAGUCAUAGCGUGGUAACAGGUACCACUGACUCAGCACCUGCCAGGCGGGUAUUAAAGGAGCCAAAAUUAAUCACCCCAUUUCUAUUCCUUACAGAGUUAGAAUCAAGGAAUAAAAAACAAAUAUUAUGAACUGCUGGCUGGGCACAGUGGCUCACGCCUGUAAUCCCAGCACUUUGGGAGGUCGAGGCAGGCAGAUCACUUAAGGUCAGGAGUUCGAGACCAGCCUGGCCGCCAUGGAGAAACCCAGUCUCUACCAAAAAUUCAAAAAUUAGCCGGGCGUGGUGGCAGGCGCCUGUAAUUCCAGGAGGCUGAGGCACAAGAAUCGCUUGAACCCAGGCAGCAGAGGUUGCAGUGACCUGAGGUCACACCAUUGCACUCCUGCCUGGGCAACAGAAUGAGACUCUGUCUCAAAAAAAAAAAACAAAAAAAAAAAAACUACUUCUAAUUAGCUCAAUAUUAAUAUUUUAACAAGUUGGGUUGGUAACAGUAUAUCUUUGCCCAUGCUGGCAAAUUCUUGUUUUGUCAGCAUUUUCCAUAACUCUGGCCAAAGUGUCACCUGAUGUGGCAACGUUUUACAGUCUUGCUAUUGUUUCUUGAGUCCUUUAAUCUAUAAGAUGUAUUUUUAAAAAUAUAUAACAUAUAAAUUUUGUUUCGUUAUAGCUCUUUAAAA